AGCGCGCGCCCGCCCGGCCCCGCGGCGGCGGCGGCGCGUCACGCUCUCCCCCGCCCCGAGCCGACGAGCCGGGAGGCGGGAGGCGGCGGCCGCGGCGGCUGCUGCUGCUGCAGUGGGACAGGUGGCGGCGACCGGCGGCGUCCGAGGAGAUUUAAUCCAGAGACUGACUUCACUAUAGAACCCACAGUUGUAUCAAUGGUUGGGGAAAGAUAGUGGCAACAGGCAAAGGAGAAACAGCUCUGACAUACAAAGAAAAUGAGUAUGCUAAAGCCAAGUGGGCUUAAGGCCCCCACCAAGAUCCUGAAGCCUGGAAGCACAGCUCUGAAGACACCUACGGCUGUUGUAGCUCCAGUAGAAAAAACCAUAUCCAGUGAAAAAGCAUCAAGCACUCCAUCAUCUGAGACUCAGGAGGAAUUUGUGGAUGACUUUCGAGUUGGGGAGCGAGUUUGGGUGAAUGGAAAUAAGCCUGGAUUUAUCCAGUUUCUUGGAGAAACCCAGUUUGCACCAGGCCAGUGGGCUGGAAUUGUUUUAGAUGAACCCAUAGGCAAGAACGAUGGUUCGGUGGCAGGAGUUCGGUAUUUCCAGUGUGAACCUUUAAAGGGCAUAUUUACCCGACCUUCAAAGUUAACAAGGAAGGUGCAAGCAGAAGAUGAAGCUAAUGGCCUGCAGACAACGCCCGCCUCCCGAGCUACUUCACCGCUGUGCACUUCUACGGCCAGCAUGGUGUCUUCCUCCCCCUCCACCCCUUCAAACAUCCCUCAGAAACCAUCACAGCCAGCAGCAAAGGAACCUUCAGCUACGCCUCCGAUCAGCAACCUUACAAAAACUGCCAGUGAAUCUAUCUCCAACCUUUCAGAGGCUGGCUCAAUCAAGAAAGGAGAAAGAGAGCUCAAAAUCGGAGACAGAGUAUUGGUUGGUGGCACUAAGGCUGGUGUAGUCCGGUUUCUUGGGGAGACCGACUUUGCCAAGGGGGAGUGGUGUGGCGUGGAGUUAGAUGAGCCACUUGGGAAGAAUGAUGGCGCUGUUGCUGGAACAAGGUAUUUUCAGUGUCAACCCAAAUAUGGCUUGUUCGCUCCUGUCCACAAAGUUACCAAGAUUGGCUUCCCUUCCACUACACCAGCCAAAGCCAAGGCCAACGCAGUGAGGCGAGUGAUGGCGACCACGUCCGCCAGCCUGAAGCGCAGCCCUUCUGCCUCUUCCCUCAGCUCCAUGAGCUCAGUGGCCUCCUCUGUGAGCAGCAGGCCCAGUCGGACAGGACUAUUGACUGAAACCUCCUCCCGUUACGCCAGGAAGAUCUCCGGUACCACUGCCCUCCAGGAGGCCCUGAAGGAGAAGCAGCAGCACAUUGAGCAGCUGCUGGCGGAACGGGAUCUGGAGAGGGCGGAGGUGGCCAAGGCCACGAGCCACGUGGGGGAGAUAGAGCAGGAGCUAGCUCUGGCCCGGGACGGACAUGACCAGCAUGUCCUGGAAUUGGAAGCCAAAAUGGACCAGCUGCGAACAAUGGUGGAAGCUGCUGACAGGGAGAAGGUGGAGCUUCUCAACCAGCUUGAAGAGGAGAAAAGGAAGGUUGAGGACCUUCAGUUCCGGGUUGAAGAAGAAUCAAUUACCAAAGGUGAUCUUGAGGUGGCUACAGUUUCAGAAAAGUCACGUAUAAUGGAACUGGAGAAAGACCUAGCAUUGAGAGUACAGGAAGUAGCUGAGCUCCGAAGAAGGCUAGAGUCCAAUAAGCCUGCUGGGGAUGUGGACAUGUCACUUUCCCUUUUGCAAGAGAUAAGCUCUUUGCAAGAAAAGUUAGAAGUCACCCGUACUGACCACCAGAGAGAAAUAACUUCUCUGAAGGAGCAUUUUGGAGCCCGGGAAGAAACUCAUCAGAAGGAGAUAAAGGCUCUGUAUACCGCCACGGAAAAGCUUUCCAAAGAGAACGAGUCAUUGAAAAGCAAGCUGGAGCAUGCCAACAAAGAGAACUCAGAUGUGAUAGCUCUAUGGAAGUCCAAACUGGAGACUGCCAUCGCAUCCCACCAGCAGGCGAUGGAAGAACUGAAGGUAUCUUUCAGCAAAGGGCUUGGAACAGAGACGGCAGAAUUUGCUGAACUAAAAACACAAAUAGAGAAAAUGAGACUAGAUUACCAACACGAAAUAGAAAAUUUGCAGAAUCAACAAGACUCUGAACGGGCUGCCCAUGCUAAAGAGAUGGAAGCCUUGAGGGCUAAACUGAUGAAAGUUAUUAAAGAAAAGGAAAACAGUCUGGAAGCCAUCAGGUCGAAACUGGACAAAGCAGAAGACCAGCAUCUCGUAGAAAUGGAAGACACGUUAAACAAAUUACAGGAAGCUGAAAUAAAGGUAAAGGAGCUAGAGGUACUGCAAGCCAAAUGCAAUGAACAAACCAAGGUUAUUGAUAAUUUUACAUCACAGCUCAAGGCUACUGAAGAAAAGCUCUUGGAUCUUGAUGCACUUCGGAAAGCCAGUUCCGAAGGUAAAUCGGAAAUGAAGAAACUUAGACAGCAGCUUGAGGCAGCUGAGAAACAGAUUAAACAUUUAGAGAUUGAAAAGAAUGCUGAAAGUAGCAAGGCUAGUAGCAUUACCAGAGAGCUCCAGGGGAGAGAGCUAAAGCUUACUAACCUUCAGGAAAAUUUGAGUGAAGUCAGUCAAGUGAAAGAGACUUUGGAAAAAGAACUUCAGAUUUUGAAAGAAAAGUUUGCUGAAGCUUCAGAGGAGGCAGUCUCUGUUCAGAGAAGUAUGCAAGAAACUGUAAAUAAGUUACACCAAAAGGAGGAACAGUUUAACAUGCUGUCUUCUGACUUGGAGAAGCUGAGAGAAAACUUAGCAGAUAUGGAGGCAAAAUUUAGAGAGAAAGAUGAGAGAGAAGAGCAGCUGAUAAAGGCAAAGGAAAAACUGGAAAAUGACAUUGCAGAAAUAAUGAAGAUGUCAGGAGAUAACUCUUCUCAGCUGACAAAAAUGAACGAUGAAUUACGUCUGAAAGAAAGAGAUGUAGAAGAAUUACAGCUAAAACUUACAAAGGCUAAUGAAAAUGCAAGUUUUCUGCAAAAAAGUAUUGAGGACAUGACUGUCAAAGCUGAACAGAGCCAGCAAGAAGCAGCUAAAAAGCAUGAGGAAGAAAAGAAAGAAUUGGAGAGGAAAUUGUCGGACCUGGAAAAGAAAAUGGAAACAAGCCACAACCAGUGUCAGGAGCUGAAAGCCAGGUAUGAGAGAGCCACUUCUGAGACAAAAACCAAGCAUGAAGAAAUCCUACAGAACCUCCAGAAGACGCUGCUGGACACAGAGGACAAGCUGAAGGGCGCACGGGAGGAGAACAGUGGCUUGCUGCAGGAGCUGGAGGAGCUGAGAAAGCAAGCCGACAAAGCCAAAUCGCUAACUUAUUUGUUAACAUCAGCCAAAAAAGAAAUUGAACUAAUGUCAGAAGAGCUGAGGGGUCUGAAAUCAGAGAAGCAGCUUCUUUCUCAGGAGGGAAAUGAUUUAAAGUUAGAAAACGGUUCACUUUUAUCCAAGCUUGUAGAAUUGGAGGCCAAAAUAGCUUUACUUCAGGGAGACCAGCAGAAACUGUGGUCAGUGAAUGAAACUCUUAAUUUAGAAAAGGAGAAAUUCUUAGAAGAAAAGCAAGAUGCCGAAAAGUAUUAUGAGCAGGAACAUCUCAAUAAAGAAGCUUUGGCUGUUGAGAGAGAGAAAUUGCUUAAAGAAAUCAAUGUUGUACAGGAAGAACUCUUGAAGAUAAAUGUGGAAAAUGACUCUUUGCAAGCUUCCAAGGUGAGCAUGCAGGCACUCAUUGAAGAGCUCCAGCUCAGCAAAGAUACUUUGAUUGCUAAGACUGAGAAGGACCAGGAAGAAAAAGAUCACCUGGAGGACCAGAUCAAGAAACUUAUUACCGAAAACUUCAUCUUGGCCAAAGAUAAGGAUGACAUCAUUCAGAAGCUUCAAAGGUCUUAUGAGGAGCUAGUCAAAGAUCAGAAAGCUUUGGUACAGGAGACUGAAGAUCUCACAGCUGAGAAAAAGUCAGCUUUAGAGAAAUUGUCCAAUCUCGAUAACACGUGCAUAGCCUUAAAGGUAGAACGAGAUAAUGUUCUUCAGAACAACAGAAAUCUGCAGUUAGAGACGGACAUGCUGCUUCAAGAUCAGGAAAAGCUGAAUGCCAGCCUCCAGGCCGCUCUCCAGGUCAAACAGCUGCUCCGCUCAGAAGCCAGUGGGCUCCGCGCACAGCUGGAUGAUGCCAGCAAGGCCCUGAGGAAGGCAGAGCUGGAGACCGUGCAACUCGAGGCCGCAAACACAAGCCUCACGAAGCUCUUGGAGGAAAUUAAGGCCAGGCGGGCGGUCACGGACUCCGAGUGCAUCCAGCUUCUGCAUGAGAAAGAAACCUUGGCUGCCUCCGAGAGAAGGCUCUUGGCUGAGAAAGAGGAACUUUUAAGUGAAAAUAGAAUAAUCACUGAAAAACUCCACAAAUGCUUAGAAGAGGCUGCCCAUACUGAGAUGAGCCUGAAUGAGAAGAUCACUUACCUGACUUCCGAGAAGGAGAUGGCUUCUCAGAAAAUGACUGAACUUAAAAAGCAGCAGGAUAGUCUCUUGAAAGAAAAAUCCUCACUGGAAACGCAAAAUGGAGCUUUACUUGCAGAGAGAGAGAAUUCCAUCAAAGCCAUAGGAGACCUCAAAAGGCAAUGUGAUCAAGAGUCUGCAAACAGAAGUUUAGUUGUGCAAGAGAAUAUGAAACUCCUCGGUAAUAUUGAUGCUCUGAAGAAGGAGCUUCAAGAGAGAAAAAAGGAAAACCAAGAACUAGUGGCCAGCAAGUGCGACCUCUCUUUGAUGCUGAAAGAGGCUCAAAAUACCAAAAAGAAUCUGGAAAAAGAACACACUCACAUAUUGCAAGCAAAGGAGAGUUUGGAUGCUCAACUUAACACGUGUUGUUCCGAGAAGAACAUUUUGCUGAGAGAUGGCUUGAACCUGCAAGAAGAGUGUCACAAAUUAAGCAAGGAGAUCCAGGAAAUGCAGCAGUCCUUAAUCCUGGAACAGGAAGCCAGAGCAAAGGAGAGCGAGUCAUCCUUGUACGAAAACAAUCAACUUCACGGGAGGAUGGUGCUCCUGGAGCAGGAGGUGGAGGAGUUAAGAGUGUGUAUCGAGGAGCUGCAGUCCGAGAAGUUUGUGCUACUUCAAGAGAAGAGCAAAUCAGAGCAAGAACUGGCAGAGAUAAUCGAGGAGAAGGAACUGUUGACUGCAGAAGCAGCUCAACUUGCUGCCCAUAUAAAGACUCUGAAAAGUGAUUUUGCUGCCUUGUCCAAAUCCAAGGCAGAGCUGCAGGAACUGCACAGCUGCCUCACCAAGAUUCUGGAUGACCUUCAGCGGAACCAUGAGGUGACCCUGGCCGAAAAAGCCCAGGUGAUGCAAGACAACCAGAACCUCCUGGCUGAGAAGAGCGAAAUGAUGCUGGAAAAGGAUGAGCUCCUGAAGGAGAAGGAAACCCUGGCAGAAAGCUACUUCAUCCUUCAGAAAGAGAUCAGCCAGUUGGCCAAAACCAACAGCCAUAUUUCAGCCAAUCUCCUAGAAUCUCAAAAUGAAAACCGUACUUUGAGAAAAGACAAGAACAAGCUUACUCUUAAAAUUAGAGAGCUCGAGACUCUUCAGUCAUUUACGGCUGCUCAAACAGCGGAAGAUGCCAUGCAGAUAAUGGAACAGAUGACCAAAGAGAAGACUGAGACUCUGGCCUCCUUGGAGGACACCAAGCAAACAAAUGCAAAACUACAGAAUGAAUUGGACACACUUAAAGAAAACAACUUGAAAAAUGUGGAAGAGCUGAACAAAUCAAAAGAACUCCUGACUGUAGAGAAUCAAAAAAUGGAAGAAUUUAGGAAAGAAAUAGAAACCCUAAAGCAGGCAGCAGCUCAGAAGUCCCAGCAGCUUUCAGCGUUGCAAGAAGAGAACGUUAAACUUGCUGAGGAGCUGGGGAGAAGCAGGGACGAAGUCACAAGUCAUCAAAAGCUGGAAGAAGAAAGAUCUGUGCUCAAUAAUCAGUUGUUAGAAAUGAAAAAAAGAGAAUCCAAGUUCAUAAAAGACGCAGAUGAAGAGAAAGCUUCCUUGCAGAAAUCCAUCAGUAUAACUAGUGCCUUACUCACAGAAAAGGAUGCCGAGCUGGAGAAACUGAGAAAUGAGGUCACAGUGCUCAGGGGAGAAAACGCCUCUGCCAAGUCCUUGCAUUCAGUUGUUCAGACUCUAGAGUCUGAUAAGGUGAAGCUCGAGCUCAAGGUAAAGAACUUGGAGCUUCAACUCAAAGAAAACAAGAGGCAGCUCAGCAGCUCCUCAGGUAAUACAGACACUCAGGCAGACGAGGAUGAAAGAGCCCAGGAGAGUCAGAUUGAUUUCCUAAAUUCAGUAAUAGUGGACCUUCAAAGGAAGAAUCAAGACCUCAAGAUGAAGGUGGAGAUGAUGUCAGAAGCAGCCCUGAAUGGGAACGGGGAUGACCUAAACAAUUAUGACAGUGAUGAUCAGGAGAAACAGUCCAAGAAGAAACCUCGCCUCUUCUGUGACAUUUGUGACUGCUUUGAUCUCCACGACACAGAGGAUUGUCCUACCCAGGCACAGAUGUCAGAGGACCCUCCCCAUUCCACACACCAUGGCAGUCGGGGUGAGGAACGCCCAUACUGUGAAAUCUGUGAGAUGUUUGGACACUGGGCCACCAACUGCAAUGACGACGAAACCUUCUGAUGAAGCCUCCAGUGGAGAACUGGGCUUGCUCAGACGCACUCGCAUUGACACAACGUAACACCAGCAUUGUGUGUGCAGACUUCAGGAGAACUCAUGUUAUUUUUUAACCCCGUCAACAAAUCUAGGAAAAUAUUUUGAUCUUCAACAAAUUGCCCUUUAGUCUCCCCGUAUGAGUUAGAAUAAUAAAUAUUUAGUAGGUGAGUUUUCACCUCGAAUUUUGUUUUCUUGAUUUUUACGUUUGAAGACAUUGCACCAGAUGCCAUUACAUUUAUUGGCCCCCCGACCUUGUAGAAAAACCCCUACCCUCACAAUACCUUAUUUAAGUAACUUUAAAUUAUGCCGUUACUUUUCAUAUUUGCACUAAGAUAUUUCCAGGCUGCAUUUGUAUAUUUAGAUUUUUUGGUUAAGCUUUGACACUGGAAUGAGUUGAAAAAAUGUGCCAUUUUGCAUUUUCAUCUACUCAUUUAAAGUAUUUUAUUCUUAUUCAAAGAAAUAUCUGAGCUCUUUGCACUACCUGUUAUCAGUAGUGCCUUUACUUCAGGCUUGAUAAUACUUAGGUGUGAUUAUAAAAUCAUGAAGCAGGUAAAGGGAGGGGCAAGCCCCCAAACUGCUGUGGGGACAUUUUAUAAUCUAUAUGCUGCACCCACUUAAUCUACUGUGGUGUUUUGUUUAUUAGUUUUGCAUAAUUUCAGCUUCUAUAUAUUGUAUGUAUAUAUUUUUUAAAAAUCUAUAUUUUGGGAAAAAAACAUACACAAUGUGUCUUUCUUUUUGGACAUUUACCUUUUUGAAAAAGAAAACACUUAAAAUGAUCAUUAGGACAUAACAGACUAGGCCAGACAUAGCAUCUUGUGGCUUUGCAACCAUUUUCAUUUGUUUGUUUUCCUUUUAUUUCUUCACCAGAUUUAAAUAACUGGAGGAAUUUUCUCCAAUUUUUUUUUCCUUCUCUGGCAGGUAUCCCCAGCAGUCAAUUAACAAUAAGCCAGUAUAAAACACCUAAAUAACCAAUCUACAAUCUCCCUUCACAAGUUUUUUUACUGUUUUUAGAUGAAUGUACGAUGAGAAAUUCAACGUUAAUAAUUCUGGAUUUUCUUAUCACAAAAAAGAAAAUGAAGGACCUCAAAGCACCUGAACAGUUUAUCGACCAGUUUGAAUCUAUUUAUCUUCAUUUGAAUGUCUUCUAGAAUAUGUAAAAAGUCAUAAAAUGUAUCUUCCAUGCUACAUGUACAAUAAGAACUUCUAUAAUUGUAUAUAUGCCUUUGAUGUAUUUUCCCCUCAAGAUUAUCAACUGUGUGUUCGACAGUGAAUAUUCAAUCUGGUACCAGUUGAAAUUUUUGGUUAUAAAUGUAAUACGAAUUGUUUCACAAACAGAAAACAUGUAAAGCAGUAUUAAAAUUUGGCCAAACAAG